GAUCCCAUCCAGGCGCUGAGAGGCAAGCCACCGGCACUCGGCGCGCAGGGCCCCGGGCACCCUCGGACCCCGUGCGGAUUUCGAGACAAGGGUCCAGAGAUAGCGGCGGCCGCCCCCAACCCGGGCCAGAGGCAGAGCCCAGGCGUGCGGUGCUUCUCGGGAACACUGGCCCUGCUACCAGAGCCGCAGGAUCCCCCAUGAGUGCCUGUGAAGGGAGUCCUGGAUAGUGAGGCCCUGGCUGGUCCAGGGGUGGGUACUCCGCCAUGCCACCCAUCCUCCAGCGCCUGCAGCAGGCCACCAAGAUGAUGAGCCGCCGGAAAAUCCUGCUGCUGGUGCUAGGGUGCAGCACCGUAAGCCUUCUCAUCCACCAGGGGGCGCAGCUCAGCUGGUACCCCAAGCUGUUCCCCUUGAGCUGCCCUCCUCUGCGGAACUCGCCGCCGCGCCCCAAGCACAUGACUGUGGCCUUCCUGAAGACUCACAAGACGGCAGGCACGACGGUGCAGAACAUCCUGUUUCGCUUUGCCGAGCGCCACAACCUGACGGUGGCCCUGCCGCACCCGAGCUGCGAGCACCAGUUCUGCUACCCCCGCAACUUCUCGGCGCACUUCGUGCACCCGGCCACGCGGCCGCCGCACGUGCUGGCCAGCCACCUGCGCUUCGACCGUGCGGAGCUGGAGCGCCUCAUGCCGCCCAGCACCGUCUAUGUCACCAUCCUGCGCGAGCCGGCCGCCAUGUUCGAGUCGCUCUUCAGCUACUACAACCAGUACUGCCCGGCCUUCCGGCGCGUACCCAACGCCUCGCUCGAGGCCUUCCUGCGCGCGCCCGAGGCAUACUACCGCGCUGGCGAGCACUUCGCCAUGUUCGCACACAACACGCUGGCCUACGACCUGGGCGGCGACAAUGAGCGCAGCCCGCGCGACGACGCCGCCUACCUGGCGGGCCUCAUCCGCCAGGUGGAGGAGGUUUUCUCGCUCGUCAUGAUCGCCGAGUACUUCGACGAGUCGCUAGUGCUGCUGCGGCGCCUACUGGCCUGGGACCUGGACGACGUGCUCUACGCCAAGCUCAACGCGCGCGCCGCCAGCUCGCGCCUGGCCGCCAUCCCCGCGGCGCUGGCGCGGGCGGCGCGCACCUGGAACGCCCUGGACGCCGGCCUCUACGACCACUUCAACGCCACCUUCUGGCGCCACGUGGCGCGCGCGGGCCGCGCGUGCGUGGAGCGCGAGGCGCGCGAGCUGCGCGAGGCCCGCCAGCGCCUACUGCGGCGCUGCUUCGGGGACGAGCCACUGCUGCGGCCUGCCGCGCAGAUCCGCACCAAGCAGCUGCAGCCGUGGCAGCCCAGCCGCAAGGUGGACAUUAUGGGCUAUGACCUGCCCGGCGGCGGCGCCGGCCCGGCCACCGAGGCCUGCCUCAAGCUGGCCAUGCCCGAGGUCCAGUACUCGAACUACCUGUUGCGCAAGCAGAAGCGCCGGGGCGGUGCGCGGGCUCGGCCCGAGCCCGUCCUGGACAAUCCCCCGCCUCGGCCCAUCCGAGUGCUGCCUCGCGGCCCUCAAGGUCCCUGAGCUCCGCAGGCCUCCAGGAGUAUGGGUCCUGCCCUGCCCUCCCAGGAGUCCAGCCAGGGGCUGCCUCCAUGUCCUGCCCCCAUGAGAGCCCUUUCUUUUCAAGGGGCUUGAGUCCCUCGCUGAACUUUGGGGUACGCCUCCCUAUCUGAGCCCCCGCUCCCGAUCGUGGGCUGAACCUUGCCUUCGGGCACGGCGCUGAUAGGCUGGAUCCAGCGCUGGGCCACCCUCUCCUUCCCAGCUGGUUGGUGAUUUUGACAAGAGGCCUGAGGGCUGUCCAGAACUGCUCACCCUGCCUUUUUCUGGGGGCUGAGCCCCCACAACCUGUCUUUUCCAAGUGGAUAAGCCCAGGCCCCAUGGAGAGAGGCUCAGCCCUAGGGAAAGGCUGCUCUUGCUCUCCCUCCCAGGGCUUGAGGCUCCCUAUACUUUUCUGUCUUCCAGGUUCUACCCUCCCCACAGACCUAAGCUGCUCCCAGUCUCCCAGAACCAAGAGUUCUUGGGUUGGGAUUUUUGUUUGGUUGGUUUUUCUUUUUUUUAAUAAAACAUCUUUAAAAUGUGCGAGUUGUAUGUCAGUCAUAGAAGCCGGAUUCCCCACAUUUGAGGAUGAAACGGAUGCCCAGGAGGAGCUGUGGCUGGACCCAUGAGGAUGGGGGCCUGGACUCAAGGUCCCCCGCCACCUGGCAUAGGCCUACAACCCUCCUCAACCGCUUGACCGACUGGGCCCCCAACACAGACUGGCCACCUUAGCCCCACUCACUUUCCACAUCGUUCUUUUUCACAAAAUUCUGCGACAUUUACUGAGCAUCAUCUCUGUAACUUGGGGAUACAGGUGAACCAGAUAGAUAGGGCCUUAUUUUCAUGGAGCUUAUGGGGAAACAUUGGAACAGGAGCAAGACAGGUAAGCAAAGAGGAAGGACUGGAGGGGUUAGAGCACAACACCUCUUUGGGUGGAAGGAGGAUCAUUUUCAGAUAAGGAGCUGCCUAACUCAGAAUUUGACCUCCUCCUGUGAAUCACUGACUUCACUAAUGGCCUGCUUUCCUCACAAGAAGACAACUUGGACUCAGAUGAAGACCAGUCCCUUUCUGCAGUUUCCUUUAACACAGCAAGAUAGCCAGCACUUCCAGGUGAAAUCUCCCUUAAGACUAGCAGAGAAUUGGAACUUUUUCUGUUACUUUCUUCAGAGCUAUAUCGACGUAUCUGGACAAGUGAUAAAAAACAAUAGCUAUUAUGGUCUACGGUGUGCCAGCCACUGUUUAAGGGCUUUAUGUAUGUUAACUUUGGAGAUGGGUGCCGUUUUCCAGGUGAGGGAACUGAAACUUGGGGGAAAUUAAGUCAGGGUCACACAGCCAGAAAGUGGCCACUAGGAUCUCAACCAAGGCAGUGUGGCUUCAGAGUUUGUGCUCACAAGUGCUGUCUGUAGUGCCAUUCAAAUAAAAAAGGUCACAUGCCACAAGCUAGGCUGAUUCCCAGCACCUUCCCCCAAAAGAAUGUAAAGGGAAGAACCAGGACACUGCUAUCAGCAACUCUUUAUCCAGUUUUUCAUGGAGACAACGGUUGACCUGUUUGGACAAUGGACAUUACAGUGAUUGAUUGGCAGGAUGCAUGACACGCUGGGCUUGAAAAGGGACUGUUUGUAUGGCACCCCACUUUUUACCAGCAGAGCUCUGAAAAAGGCAAUAAUUAGAAUCAUGCAAAAGCAUAAUUAAGUUUCUGACAUUAAGCAGCAGUAAAGAAUUGUACCAGA